AGGGGCCGGGGCCGAGCGGGAACCCAGGCCGGGGGCUUCCCAGGGCGGCUUCGAAACGGGCAGUCGAGGCGGGCGAGGGCUCGGCUGCUCCUGCGGGCGUCUGUGCAGAUGCUGAGGCUGUUGACCAAAACAGCGCAAGGAAGGAAUCCGCGAGAAGCUCAGAUUCGCGGGGGAGGCCCUGCUGCCGGGAGGGGAGGGAGAGGCACAGCGGGGCCCUAGCGCGGGCUCUAGCCGGGAGCUGUAGCGUGGCUGUAGGUGUGCAUCUGUGGAGCUGGUAGAGUUCCGCAGCGCAGGAGGGAGGCUGCUGGAGGUGCACAUCAGUUACUUUGAAAUGUGGUGGAAAUGGUGAUGGAUGGGAUUUAUUCAGUCCACAUCGGUUCAGAGGCCAGCAAGGUGCUGCUGGGUGUGACUGGUGCUGGGCCAGGCAUGAUCUUGGCGUUGAGGGAGUUGAUGCCCCAGCAGGGGAGACAGGCACCAGAUGCACAAUUGUUUGACCACAGUUGGGACAAAGGCUAAGGCACGGGUUCCAGGAACUUGUAGGAUGCGGCUGUGGGAGUGGUGUCAGAUGCUGAGGGUGUGAGUUGAACUGUGGAGAAUUUCUCUGGAAAUUAGCCAGAGAAAAAGUGAGGUUCCGGGGCAGCCAGCCGUGUGCGGCUCCAGGCAGAAGAAACAGAAUGCACAGACCCUUAGUGGUAGGCGAUGAUGACGUAUAGGAGCUGAAAGAUUGUCCUGGCUAAGGCACAGAGAGCCACCGGAGAAGGGACACGGUAACGUGUAGAGGGGAGUGGAGGGUGAGGACAAGCUUCAGGAUGGGAGAAGAGCCACAAAGGAGACUGAGAGGGGGCUGGUAGGAGAAACCAGGACACUAGAAUGUGUCGAAACCAAGAGGAUGGAGUUUAAAGGAGGAGGGAGCCAUCAGCAGUGCUGAACAAAAGAGCAGCUGAAAAGAUCCCACUGACCGCAGCAGCCGAGCUUUUGUGACCUUUAGGGGUCACUGCGGAGGCCGGGCUGGAGCCAGGUAGCCUGAGUUAGGAUGCACACCUGGGCAGGUAGAGAUAGCUUGCUCCAGCUUUUAGGAGGACAGGGGCAGAGUGGACAGGAACUUAGUUUGGGGAAAACUUGAACAUGUUCAGGAUGCUGGAGAGGAGCGUUCCACUGCUGCCGAGGUUGGAGAUCCAAGAGCAGGGAUGAAUUUAACUCCCCCUCCCUCUAGCGUGCUGUAUACCGAAACAGAGUGAAAGUGAUCCAUAAACUUACGUAGUUUAUUCGAUCAACAUGAUUGGCCCGCCAGCCCCGGGUAAGUUGACCCUAAGGACAUUUUAAGAGUAAUUUCUUUCCAUUUUACAUAUGGGUAUCCUUGGUGCCAGAUUAUAUGAGUCGUAUUUCACAAGGUCACAAUUAAAGUGUUUGAGACUUUUUUAUAGUUUAGAGAUUUUAUUUGCUGUUUCCACUGGAUUGUCCAGAUUUUUAUUUCAAGAAUUGUGUACAUUUUAACAGAAAUAAUGAAACCUAGAAAAUGCCUUCCCCCCACCCCAUGUACACACUUUAAAAGCUGGCCUUAAUAAUUUAAUUUGCAUGAUGUGGUAAGCCUCAGUGAAGGUUGUGAGCUUGAAGGGCGGCCCUAGUUCCAGUGUAUCCACCUUGAUUAGAUUGACCUGGGUUCAGUCCUGUCUGGGUGCACUCGAAGCUUCUUGCCAACGUCUGGGCCUUUGUUAAUUUGACCUGGGUUCAGUCCUCUCUUGGUGCACUCAAAGCUUACUGCCAAUGUCUGGGCCUUUGUAAAUUUGAUCUGGGUUUAGUCCUGUCUAGAGGGACUCGGCUUCCUUCUCUCCCCUGUAGUUUUUUAGUUGACGAGCCUUUUUGUUUCCUAAGAAGCUUUAUGCCAGUUCCCUUUUUCACAAGAGGUAACUUGGGUCUCUCAGUCACUUUUGGACAUGAAGCACCUAGUCUUUAGACUUAGCUAUCGAUCAUUGCUUUAAUCACUGUUAUUUUAUGGAGAAACCUGUAAGGGGUGACAUCAAAUGAUUGCAGCUUUGUUGACUGACCAGAGGCCUGUUAAUGGACUAAGCCUAGACCCCAAAGCUUCUCUUGCUCCUUCAGAACCAGUGCCUUGGCACCACCGUGUGGUUCAGGGUUUACUGGAGUAUCUUGUGACAUCAGACAAUUUGAGUAGAUUGCAGGGGGCUCUUCGUGUUUCUGGAUACCGACUUCUGUCCACUCUAGCUAACAGUAGUGAUUCAAAGCCAUUUUGAGUGGCCUGGAUCCAUGUGCUCCUGCAUCUGUUCUUCUAGAGUUCCAAGAAAUUAGGCUGCUGGUGUUAUGGUGUUGUCACACAUUAGGGGAGGCUUCAAGGGGUUAUCGGCAGGAGCUCAAGAUCAGACACCAUCAUAUCUUCCAGAUUUGCACAUUCCUGGUGUGGAGUCAUCAGUUGUAUAAUGCUGGUUAAAUAAUUCAGUCGCCGAAGAGUAUAUUAGUCUGCUGAUUGGUCUUGGAGGGUCUGAGGGUACAAUGUUGAAUUUUUUUAGGUGAAAUUCAUAUAACAUAAAAUUAACUAUUUUAAAGUGUACAAUUCAGUGGUGUUUAGUACGUUCACAAAUUUGUGGAACCACUACCUCUAUCUAGUCCUAAAACAUUUUUGUCACCCCGAACGAUAACUGUACCCAUUAGCAGUCACUCCCAACUCCUCCCUUGCCCCAGCCCCUGGCUACCACUCACCUUUCUCUCUAUAUAGAUGUGCCCAUUCUGGAUAUUUCAUAUAAGUGAAAUCGUACACUGUGUGGCUGGAAUCGCACACUGUGCGGCUGGACUCAUGCACUGUGCGGCUGGAGUCGUGCACCGUGUGGCUGGACUCGUGCACUGUGGCUGGAGUCGUACACUGUGCAGCUGGAGUCGUGCGCUGUGUGGAUGGAAUCAUACACUGUGUGGCUUCUUGUGCCUGGUUUCUUUUACUCAGUGUCAAAAGUUCAUCCAUGUGGCAUGUAUCAAUACUUCAUUCCUUUUUAUGGCCGAAUUAUGUUCCGUUAUAUGGAUAUAGUAAAUGUUGUUGUAUAACCAUGGCAGAUUUUUAAAUCUAGCAACGAUGACCACUUCCAUAAUAAGGGCGUCAUGGCUGUUCCUGGUGGUGGACCAUUUUGGGGGCUGCACUUCUGUCUUUAUCCUAAGGUUUUUGAGGUAAUUCUUGGCUUUGCUCACCCUCCCUUGGGAAGGCUGUCAACUUCAUAAAAAGACUCUAGCUGUAUCUUUUGUCAGCUUACGGUCAGAGACUAUGGGAUCUGCCUUAAUUUAGCUAAAUUUGAUCUUACCAGAGAAUACAACCUUGAAUUUUUUGUUUAGUUCUUUUCAAAAGCUCAGUUUCAGGAAAUAAUGUAGUGAAUAUGUAUUCCAUUUAUUCCUCUAGAAUCUAGAUCGGGGUCGGCAAACUACAGCCCACAGGCUAGCUGUCUGUUUUUGUAAAUUGAGUUUUAUUGGAACACAGCCUACGGCUGUCUGCUUUGGCAACAGACCCACAGGCCUGAGAUGGCAGAGAUGGCUGCUGUCUGGAACAUUAAGAGACAAAGUUGGCUGAAUGAAGGCUUCUGAUCUUCUUCAUCCGUUCUUAAUCUGAGUUCUACCUUCCCCUUGUGAGGACUUUGCAGAUGGGCUUAAGCCAUCUGUGAAACCCCUGAAAUUUUAUGCAAAGCUGCCUGCACGUGUGAGGGCCAUAUAUGUUUUCCUGGAGGGCGGACCUGUGACUCCUCAGAUUCCAAAAGGGAUCCAAGACUCCCAAAUGCUCAACACUCAUUGUUUGAGUAGCCGAAAUGUUAAUUGCCUAGCAUCACCUGAAUUAGCCAUUCUCUUAAGUGUUUAGUCUCAGGAGUUCGAUGUGGUUUUUGGGUUUGUUUUUUGUUUUCUAACUUUUAGGUUCAGGGGUACAUGUGCAGGUUUGUUAUAAAGGUCAACUGUGUGUCAUGGGAGUUGGUGUACAGAUUAUGUCGUCAACCAGGUACUAAGCACAGUAGCCGGUGGGUAGUUUUGGGAUCCUCUCCCUCCUGCCACCCUCAAGCAGGCCCUGGUGUCUGUUGGUCCUUUUUUGUGUCCACGCCUGCUCAGUGUUCAGCUCCCACUUACAAGUGAGAACAUGUGGCAUUUGGUUUUCUGUUCCUGCGCCAGUUCACUUAGGAAAAUGGCCUCCAGCUCCAUCCAUGUUGCUGCAAAGGACACAAUCUCGGUCCUUUUUAUGGCUAUGUAGUAUGCCAUGGUAUAUAUGUAGCACAUUUCCUAUAUGUUUUUAAGAAUGAUUGGAACCCCAGUCAUUCUUAAAUGAGAGUUCUUGUUUGUGUGGGUAAUAGUCAUCAAUAUUGACCAUAUUAGAAAUUAAAAUAGUAUUAAAAUAUUUCUAUAGUUAAUUAGCAAUAAAAACCCAUUACAUUUUUGCAAAUAUCUUAAUGUCUGGCUUGAUAAAAGAUAGGCUCUCGAAUCUCGCGUUCAUUCCUGUGAUAUCACAGGCCUUGCAGCCCACGGAGGCCUCUGCUGUGCACUCUGUGAGAAUGAGAGUGAGCAAGGCUGGUGGCGGCUUAGGACGCUCGGGAAGGUAGUUCUGUGGGACUCCUGAAAGGCCUCAGGACCCAGGAUCCCAGAUGCACACGGGAGAGUAUGUAUCUGGACAGCGUUAUCUUAAUGCCUCUGCAGAAUCGUCCUCUGGUAUUUUGGCAUCAGCAUGCUUUUUGAUUGCCUGUCUCAAAAAAAAAAAAACUUCUGGAAGCUGGCUCUGCUGUACGUGGUUGGCAUUUUGGUGAGGAAUUGGUAUGUGUGAGGGGACAUUGAACUUUGUGAGGAGCCGCAGAAGACGUUUCCUCAGGUUUUAGGCCAGAAGGGUCUGUAUCUGUACCACUUCUGAGCUGCUGAAGACUGUGCAGUCUUUGUAACUGAUGAAGAGCAAGGCUUUGUCUCUAAUUCUGCCCAGUUAAAGUGCAGGCGUUAGGCUAAAGCUGGGACAAACCUGGAGCGGCUUCAUUGGCUUUCCUACUUCUUUUGCAUCCCAAAGCAUAAGCUUAAAUCGUCUCAGAAGGACAAGGUCCGCCAGUUUAUGGCGUGCACUCAGGCUGGCGAGAGAACUGCUAUCUACUGCUUAACGCAGAAUGAGUGGAGACUAGACGAGGCCACGGACAGCUUCUUCCAAAACCCAGACUCGCUCCACAGGGAGUCCAUGCGGAACGCUGUGGACAAGAAGAAGCUGGAGCGGCUGUACGGCAGGUACAAAGAUCCACAAGAUGAAAACAAAAUUGGAGUCGAUGGGAUUCAACAGUUUUGUGAUGAUCUGAGCCUGGAUCCUGCCAGUAUCAGUGUAUUGGUCAUAGCGUGGAAGUUCAGGGCAGCAACUCAGUGUGAAUUUAGCAGAAAGGAAUUUCUAGAUGGCAUGACAGAACUUGGGUGUGACAGCAUGGAGAAGCUAAAGGCUCUUCUGCCAAGACUGGAGCAGGAGCUGAAGGACACAGCCAAGUUUAAAGAUUUUUAUCAGUUUACCUUCACCUUCGCUAAGAACCCAGGGCAGAAAGGUUUAGACUUAGAAAUGGCUGUUGCGUAUUGGAAAUUAGUGUUAUCUGGAAGGUUUAAAUUUUUAGAUCUCUGGAACACAUUCUUAAUGGAACAUCACAAAAGAUCAAUUCCAAGGGACACCUGGAACCUCCUGCUGGACUUUGGAAACAUGAUUGCGGAUGAUAUGUCUAACUACGAUGAAGAAGGAGCUUGGCCCGUUCUUAUAGAUGAUUUUGUAGAAUAUGCACGGCCAGUAGUCACAGGUGGAAAACGCAGCCUUUUCUAGGCAGCAAGUUAAGCAGGAGUAAGAUUAUGAAAUGAUUUGUAUCCUGCAAGGAGAUUGCAGUCAGUUCCUGGGUGCAUUGUCGCUGAUUCCAGAAGUCAUUCUUGACCAGCCAUGAAACCAGAGGCGCCAUCCCAUUCUGCCGGAGGACAGCCAGCGGCUGCUUUGUGGACACCGCAGGAAGUUCCUCGGGACACGGCUGCUUUGGGAUGUUUGGAGAUUUGUCAUCAUAGCUUUUGCGUUAGGAAAUUUCUGCAUGAUUUUUUAAUAUUUACAAAAUACUAAGGUAGAGCCAUAGCGCCGCCUGUGGGACCGCAGAGCAUGCUGCGUAGCUCGCGCGUCAGGCGAACCAGCGUCCGGCAGCGUCCCGCCGAAUGACGUUGCGGUGGCACUGGCAACACGGCAUGUGUCCUCUGCAGGGCGCUGCGUUUUUAUACACGUCAAAGCUGUUAAGAAUGUGCCCUAAGGGAGAGGAUCUUGUCGUAGAGUCUAAUGUUUUUUAAAAUUGGUGCCAGCAAUUCACGAUUUAUAUUUUUUGAAUUACCAAAUAUCUAGAUUUACCAGCUCUAUUUUUGUUUUCAUUUUCUCUAGACAUUCAUCUGAAAAUCAUUUUAUGGUUCUCAAUCCCCAUGUAGCUUUGCAUAGCAACGGCACACGUGGCACGAUUCCAGCAGAGUUUAUCUCACACCGUUUAUAUAUCACUGGGCCUCUCUUACUUAAAUAUUAUUUGACCUGCCUGAGAAGCUUCAUAAAGUAUGUUUUUUUAAAAUAUAUUUUAAUUACAUUUAAAAAGACAUUUUUCCAUGAAAAACAUUUAUUUUAUGAGUGAUGAAUUAUAGAUUUUAAAAUCAAGGCCGGGCGUGGUGGCUCACACCUGUAAUCCCAGCAUUUUGGGAGGCCGAGGCAGGUGGAUCACCUGAGGUCAGGAGUUUGAGACCAGCCUGGCCAACAUGGUGAAACCCUGUCUCUACUAAAAAUACAAAAAUUAGCCGGGCAUGGUGGCACAUGCCUGUAAUCCCAGCUACUCAGGAGGCUGAGGCAGGAGAUUCGCUUGAACUCAGGAGACGGAGGUUACAGUGAGUCGAGAUCGCGCCACUGCACUCCAGCCUGGACGACAGAGUGAGAUUCUGUCUCAAAAUAAAUACAUACAUACAUACAAUAAAACCGAAUGAGCUGGUUCUUUCCAUCCUCUUGUGGUACCCGUAGUGCCCAGCAUCCAGACCUUUGUGCCCCUGUGCACAUUUGGAAGCUAAAAUGUACAUCGUUGUCUGAAAAAACCCAACCCCAAAACCUUCAUCUGAUUGGUGAGCUGAAGUCUGUCCUUGCACCAUGUUAUCAUCUGUUUCUCGUGUCCGCCUGGUUGAGGAGGACCCACGAGUGCUGCCGAGGUGUGGAGGGCUGGUAUUGAGUUGUGGACAUCACUGUUGACCCUACCUCACGUGCCGAGACUCUCAUGUCACAGGCGUGCCUUGCUGCCCCCCUGCAGCACUGUGCAGGACGUGGACCAGCUGGAGCUGCUGCCCAGCACAGAGGAGAGUCGCCGCAGAUGACCUAGCUGCGGUGUGAGAGAGCAUGGCCCAGACAAGCAGCUGGGUUGGCUUCUGAGAACAGGACUUACCCUGGGCUUCAGGAACAUCUGAUGGCUGAGGUUAGUGUGCUUGGAGGCUGCAGGACGAACUGUCGAUGUUUCUUAGCAGAGAUGGUCACAGAGGGCAGCAGGGACAGGACUGGAAGGGACCUGCAGCCUGCAGACCCCGCCUGGCCCCCGCUGGCUUCUGGCUGGUCCAGUGAUGGGCAAGUGACAGACCUUCCCCAGGCUCUGCUUCCAGAACUCUAAUGGGAAACUGGGCCUGUCUACCUUUAGAAGUCUUCGAUUCUCAGAGAGCAUUUGUCUAAUACAAUAAAAACUGGCAUUAAUACAAACCUCAAAAACGUGAGCGUAUCUUCCAGGCUUCAUGGAUUCUUGACAUGUAAUUGUUUUGUUCAGAAAAGUUUAUAGAAUUCACAUAAUUCUGUAUAAACUAUGGAGAUCCACAGUACUUUUUUGUUUUUGAGAUUUAAAGUUCUAAGGGAUUGUCAAUAGAUAUCAAAAUAUUAAUCAUUGGACAAAGGCUUUUCCAAAAAUUGUGGGUUUUUUUCUUCUGUUGUAUCCAUUUGAGUCCUGCAUGCUGUGAAAUGCUGAGAACAGAAGCAUUAAAUUGGUUUUUCUCGGG